GCUUUUGCUCGGACCUGGAGUAAUGAGAGUGGACGUUUGAUUCCAACAGGAUGGCCCAUUUCUCCAGCGAGGACCAGGCGAUGCUGCAGGCGAUGCUGAGGCGGUUGUUCCAGAGCGUGAAGGAGAAAAUCACGGGUGCCCCUUCCCUGGAGUGUGCCGAAGAGAUUCUUUUACAUCUGGAGGAAACUGAUGAAAAUUUUCACAACUAUGAAUUUGUGAAAUACCUCAGGCAGCAUAUAGGCAACACUUUGGGUUCUAUGAUUGAAGAAGAAAUGGAAAAAUGCACAUCUGAUCGGAAUCAGGGUGAAGAAUGCGGCUAUGAUACAGUUGUACAGCAGGUCACUAAAAGAACUCAAGAAUCUAAAGAGUACAAAGAAAUGAUGCAUUACCUGAAGAACAUUAUGAUAGCUGUGGUCGAGUCUAUGAUUAACAAGUUUGAAGAAGAUGAGACACGAAAUCAAGAAAGGCAGAAAAAAAUCCAAAAGGAGAAAAGCCAUAGUUACCGCACAGACAAUUGCUCUGAUAGUGAUUCAUCAUUGAAUCAGAGUUACAAAUUUUGUCAAGGAAAAUUACAAUUGAUUUUAGACCAGUUGGAUCCUGGGCAACCUAAAGAGGUGAGAUAUGAAGCCUUGCAAACAUUAUGUUCAGCUCCUCCAUCUGAUGUCCUCAACUGUGAAAAUUGGACUACUCUCUGCGAAAAACUGACCGUGUCUCUUUCAGAUCCUGAUCCUGUGUUUAGUGACCGGAUUUUAAAAUUCUGUGCACAGACAUUUUUGCUUUCUCCAUUACAUAUGACCAAGGAAAUUUAUACAAGCUUAGCUAAGUAUUUGGAGUCAUACUUUCUUUCUAGGGAAAAUCAUAUUCCUACUCUUUCAGCUGGUGUAGAUAUAACUAAUCCUAAUAUGACUCGCUUACUUAAAAAGGUUCGUCUUCUAAAUGAAUAUCAGAAAGAAGCUCCAUCUUUCUGGAUUCGUCAUCCAGAGAAGUAUAUGGAAGAAAUUGUGGAGAGUACUUUGUCCUUGUUAACAGUUAAACAUAAUCAAAGCCAUGUUGUCUCACAAAAGAUUUUGGAUCCGAUCUACUUUUUUGCAUUAGUUGAUACCAAGGCUGUGUGGUUCAAAAAGUGGAUGCAUGCACAUUAUAGCAGAACUACAGUAUUAAGACUUCUUGAAACGAAAUAUAAGUCUCUGGUAACUACAGCCAUUCAACAGUGUGUUCAGUACUUUGAAAUGUGUAAGACUAGGAAAGCUGAUGAAACUUUGGGACAUUCAAAGCAUUGCAGAAACAAGCAGAAAACUUUCUACUACUUAGGACAAGAAUUACAAUAUAUUUAUUUCAUUCACUCACUGUGCCUUUUAGGAAGAUUAUUGAUCUAUAAACAAGGCAGAAAACUAUUUCCUAUUAAGCUGAAGAAUAAAAAAGGUUUGGUAUCCCUCAUAGAUCUGCUUGUUCUUUUUACCCAACUUAUCUAUUACUCACCAAGUUGUCCAAAGAUGACAUCAGCUGCCCAUUCAGAGAAUUACUCUCCUGCAAGUAUGGUGACUGAAGUUCUGUGGAUACUCAGUGAUCAAAAAGAAUGUGCAGUGGAAUGCUUAUAUAACAACAUUGUAAUAGAGACACUUCUUCAGCCUAUUCACAAUUUAAUGAAAGGAAAUGAGGCAUCUCCAAAUUGCUCUGAGACAGCUUUAAUUCAUAUAGCUGGUAUUUUGGCAAGAAUUGCAUCUGUAGAAGAAGGGCUUAUUUUACUCCUUUAUGGAGCAAAUAUGAACUCUUCUGAAGAAAGUCCUACAGGUGCUCAUAUAAUUGCCCAGUUUUCGAAAAAACUUCUCGAUGAAGAUAUUUCUAUAUUUUCUGGAUCAGAAAUGUUGCCUGUGGUUAAAGGAGCUUUUAUUUCUGUGUGUCGUCACAUAUAUAGUACAUGUGAAGGUUUGCAGGUGUUAAUCACUUAUAAUUUGCAUGAAUCUAUAGCAAAGGCAUGGAAAAAGACAAGUUUGCUAUCAGAAAGAAUUCCUACUCCAGUAGAGGGUUCUGAUUCUGUUUCUUCAGUAAGCCAGGAAUCCCAAAACAUUAUGGCUUGGGAAGAUAAUUUGUUAGAUGAUUUACUACAUUUUGCUGCCACCCCCAAAGGAUUACUACUUCUUCAAAGAACAGGUGCUAUCAAUGAAUGUGUGACAUUUAUAUUCAAUCGAUAUGCAAAAAAAUUACAGGUCAGCAGGCAUAAAAAAUUUGGCUAUGGAGUUUUGGUUACACGAGUGGCAUCAACAGCAGCAGGUGGCAUUGCACUAAAAAAGUCAGGGUUUAUUAAUGAACUUAUAACUGAAUUAUGGUCCAAUCUGGAAUAUGGAAGAGAUGAUGUUAGGGUAACCCAUCCCAGAACUACUCCAGUGGAUCCUAUUGACCGAAGCUGUCAAAAGACCUGCCUUUCAAAUAAUGAUGAAGAAAAUUCUUCAUGUUGAAAGACAGUGCUACCAGAUGGAUAGCUGGAUUUUCAGGAUGGAAACAGGGAAUUGCAAAUAGGUAAGUGAGUAUAGAAGCCUAUUAUUUUUCCUUUUAACUUAUUUUAAAUACAUAUGAUUGGUUUUUUAAAACAAAAUUAUGAUACAUAGUGGGGUUUAUUUUGUACUUAGAAAUAAAAUCGUACAUAGGAUAGCUGUAGCAUAAAGGACAGGGGAAUUGUAUAAUGGUAAAUCAAUCUAUAUGGUUCAACUUCCUCACAUUUUAUAUAAAAUGGCACAAUAUUCCUAAUCCCUUGGAAAUAUUUAUAAUUCAAAUAGAAGGUUACAGGGAUUUUAUUCAAUUUGUUUGACUUUGCAAUAGAAAUGUCAGUAUAAACUAAGGAUUUUUUAAAAAAUAUUUUGUAUUCUGCUAAUCUAUAUACAGAAAGACCUAGAAAUGACAACUCAUUGUAGUAAACAGCCCUAGAGUCCAGCUUCUAGUCUCUAAGUCUUAUUCCCUAAGGGAUUCUUUUUUCAUUUAUAAUCUAAUUUGGUCUUUUAAAUUGUGGAAAACAGUUAUGUAGUUUCGAUAUAUAACUAGAUACCUUCAGAAACAUAUGUCCAUUCUAGUCCCCAUCCUUCAUCUUCCCUCUGUGGCUUCUGUUAAACAUGGUAGACAAUUGCCCUAUGCAGCUAUACAAACUUGUAUUAAUUAAAAUUAAAAAUUCAGUUCCUUAAUUAUAUUAGUCAUAAGUGCUCAAUAGCACAUGUAGCUAGUGGUUACCAUAUUGUAAAAUUCAGGUUAUAUAAUAUUUCUAUCAUUACAGAAAGUUCUAUUGGACAGUACUUCCUUAGGAAAGCACUAAAAAUUAGUGCAAAGAGGUAUAGCUCAUACAUAAAUUUUACAAUUAAAAAAAAAAAACAAAAAUAAAAACACAAACCAAACACAGAAUAAGGUGGGGAGGAAAGAAUAAAAGAACAGGAAAUGGAUGGAAAAAAAGAAAACAAGUAGGAAAAUAGUAGCUCUAAAUGCAUCCAUAUCAAUAAUUACACUAAAUGCAAAUGAACUAAAUAUUCUAAUUAAAAUACAGAUUUUCAGCAUGUAUAAAAAAGGAAGAUACAACUAUGUGCCAUCUUUAAGAAAUUAACUUUAGGAUUAAGAUGGUGGAUAGGAGGUAGGACUAGCUUGCAGCUCCUGCUCAGACAGACAGAACAUUGUGUGGAGACUUACAUCGUGAACUGUUGCUUCAAGAACUACCACAGGAACAUACUAGGAAAGAUGACAGAAUCCACAGAACCUUUGAAGGAACUGGAUCACUGCUGCAGGCUCACUGAGAUGUGGAAAAACUGAGUCUGCUUGCUUUCUCAACAAAGAGGCUUGUGGUCUGGGUCAAGUUCUCCGCCCUGAUCACCAGCUGCCUGGAAAUAGACUUGGUGCUGUUGAGGGGCAAGAUAGGAGUGAGACCGGCAUUUAGGACUGUCAGCUGCAUGAGAGCAUGGUGAGGCUGGUGACUGCCAGCUUUCCUCACUUGCCUGGUGAUUUGUAUGACUCAGGAGAGGCAGCCAUAAUCCCCCUGGAAAUAUAACUCCAUUGGACUGGGAACCACUCACCCAUCCCCCACAGCAGCCACAGCAAACUUCGCCCAAGGAGAGGCUGAGCUCAGACACGCCUCUCCCUGCCCCCUCCUGGUGGUCUUUUUUUACCCUCCCUGGUAGCUGAAGACAAAGGUCAUAAUCUCUUUGGAACUCUAUGGCCCUGCCCACUGCCUGAGAAUCCUGAAUGCUUAACCAGGUGUCCCUAGGGCAAGGUUGCAUCCUCCCUACAGGAUCACAGCUGAUGCCCUCUUGAAAGUGCCACCUCCUGGCUGGAGGCCAAGCAACACAAAACCAGCACACUAAACAAAAACACAACCAAGGAGCCUCACAGAGUGACUCCCCUGCCACCUCCACCAGAGCAGGUACUGAUAUCCAUAGCUGCAAGACCUGAAGACGGAUCACAUCACAAGACCCUUUGCAGGCACUCCCUACUACCAGCCCAGAGCCCGGUAGCUCUGCUGGAUGGCUAGACCCAGAAGAGCAAAAACAAUUACUAUAGUUCAGCUCUCAGGAAGCCCCAUUCCUAGGGGAAGAGGAGAACACUACAUCAAGUAGUGUUGGGAUAACAGAAUCUGAACAGCAGCCCUUGAAUCCCACAUCUUCCCUCUGACGUAGUCUACUCAAAUGAGAAGGAACCAGAAAAUGAUUCUGGUAAUAUGACAAAAUAAGUUUCUUUAACACUCCCAAAUGAUCAUACCAGCUCAUCAGCAAUAGAUCCAAACCAAGACAAAAUCUCUGAAUUGCCAGAAAAAGAAUUCAGAAGGUUGAUUACUCAGCUAAUCAAGGAGUCAUCAGAGAAAGAUGAAGUCCAACUUAAAGAAAUAAAAAACAUGAUACAGGAUAUGAAAGGAAAAUUCUUCAGUGAAAUAGAGAGCACAAAUUAAGAACAAUCACAACUUCUGGAAAUCAAGGAUACACUUAGAGAAAUGCAAAAUGCACUGGAAAGUCUCAGUAAUAGAAUCGAACAAGCAGAAGAAAGAACUUCAGAGCUCAAAGACAAGGCUUUCACAUUAACUCAACCCAUCAAAGAUAAAGAAAAAAAUUUUUAAAAAUGAACAAAGCCUCCAAGAGGCUUGGGACUAUGCUAAAUGUCUGAGCCUAAGAAUAAUUGGUGUUCCCUAGGAAGAAGAGAAAUUUGAAAGUUUGGAAAACAUAUUUGAGGUAAUAAUAAAGGAAAACUAACCCCAGCCUUGCUAAGGAUCUAGACAUCCAAAUACAAGAAACUGAAAGAACACCUGGGAAAUUCAUCGCAAAAAGAUCAUUGCCUAGGCAUAUGGUCAUCAGGUUAUCUAAAAUCAAGAUGAAGGAAAAAAAUCUUAAGAGCUGUGAAGCAAAAGCAUUAGGUAACUUAUAAAGGAAAACCUAUCAGAUUAACAACAGAUUUCUCACCAGAAACCCUACAAGCUAGAAGGGAUUGGGGUCCUAUUUUUAGCCUCAUUAAACAAAACAGUAUCAGCCAGAAUUUUUUAUCCAGUAAAACUAGGCUUCAUCAAUGAAAGAAAGAUACAGUCUUUUUCAGACAAACAACUGCUGAGAGAAUUCACCACUACCAAGCCAGCACUAUAAGAACUGCUAAAAGGAGCUCUAAAUCUUGAAACAAAUUCUCGAAAUACACCAAAAUAGAACAUCCUUAAAGAAUAAAUCUCACAGCACCUAUCUAACAAAAACACAAUGACAAAAAAACCAAGGUAUUCAGGGAACAAAUAGCUUGAUGAAUAGAACAGUACCUCACGUCUCAAUACUAUCGUUGAAUGUAAAUGGCCUAAAUGCUCCACUUAAAAGAUACAGAAUGGCAGAACGGAUAAGAAUUUACUAACCAAGGUACUGCUAUCUUCAGGAGACUCACCUAACCCAUAAGGACUCACAUAAACUUAAGAUAAAGGGGUGGAAAAAGAUAUUCCGUGCAGUGGACACUAAAAGUGAGCAGGAGUAGCUAUUCUUAUAUCAGACAAAGCAAACUUUAAAGCAACAGCAGUUAAAAAGACAAAGAAGGAUAUUAUAUAAUGAUAAAAAGACUAGUCCCACAGGAAAAUAUCAAAAUCCUAAAUAUAUAAGCACUUAGCACUGGAGCUCCCUAAUUUAUAAAGCAAUUACUAGUAGACCUAAGAAAUGAGAUAGAUGGCAACACAAUAAUAGUGUGGAACUUUAAUACUCCAUUGACAACACUAGACAGGUCAUCAGGAUAGAAAGUCAACAAAGAAGCAGUGAAGUUAAACUAUACCGUAGAACAAAUGGACUUAACAGAUAUUUACAGAACAUUUUACCGAACAACUACAGAAUAUACAUUCUUUCAUCAACACAUAGAACAUCCUCCAAGAUAGACCAUAUGAGAGGCCACAAAAACAAGUCUCAGUAAAUUUAAGAAAAUCAAAAUUAUAUCAGGUACUCUCUCAGACCACAGUGGAAUAAAAUUGGAUAUUAACUUCAAAAGGAACCCUCAAAACCAUGCAAAUACAUGGAAAUUAAAUAACCUGCUCCUAAGUGAUCAUUGGACCAACAAUGAUAUCAAGAUGGAAAUUAAAAACAUUUUUGAACAAAUGAUAAUAGUGACAAAACCUCUAGAUACAGCAAAAGCGGGGCUAAGAGGAAAGUUUAUAGCAUUAAAUGCCUACAUCAAAAUGCCUGAAAGAGCACAAAUAUACAAUCAAAUGUCACAACUCAUGGAACUAGAGAAACAAGAAUAAUCCAAAACCAAACCCAGCAGGAAAAAAGAAAUAAUGAACACCAAGCUGAGAAUCAAAUAAAAAAUUCAACCUGGUUUACAAUAGUUGCAAAAAUAAAUAAAUAAAUAAAAUACUUAGGAACAUACCUAACCAAAGACAUGAAAGACCUCUACAGGGAAAACUACAAAACACUGCUGAAAGAAAUCAGACAACACAAACAAAUGGAAAGACAUUUCAUGUUCAUGAAUGGGUAGAAUCAAUAUUGUGAAAAUGGCUAUACUUCCCAAAGCAAUUUACAGAUUCAAUGCAAUUCCUAUCAAAAUACCACCAUAAUACUUCACACAACUAGAACAAACAAUCCUAAAAUGUAUAUGGAGCCAACAAAGAGCCCGCAUAGCCAAAGCAAGACUAAGCAAAAAGAACAAAUCUGGAGGCAUCACAUUACCCAACUUCACAUUAUUUUACAAGGCUACAGUUAACAGAAUGACGUGGUACUGGUAUAAAAAUAGGCACACAGACCAAAUGUAACAGAAAUAGAGAACUCAGAAAUAAAGCCAAAUACAGCCAACUGAUCUUCGACAAAGUAAACAAAAACAUAAAGUGGUAAGUAUACCCUAUUCAAAAAAUAGUGCUGGGGUAAUUAGCAAGCCACAUGUAGAAGAAUGAAACUGGAUCCUCAUCUCUCACCUUAUAUAGAAAAAUCAACUCUAGAUCAAUCAAACACUUAAAUCUAAGAUCUGAAACCAUAAAGAUUCCAGAAGAUAACAUCAGAAAAACCAAAUCCUUCUAGACAUUAGCUUAGGUAAAGACUUUAUGACUAGGAAUUCAAAAGCAAAUGCAAGAAAAACAAAGAUAAAUAGAUGGGACUUAAUUAAAUUAAAAAGCUUCUGCCCAGCAAAA